GGUCUGAGUGCAGAGCUGCUGUCAUGGCGGCCGCUCUGUGGGGCUUCUUUCCCGUCCUGCUGCUGCUGCUGCUAUCGGGGGAUGUCCAGAGCUCGGAGGUGCCCGGGGCUGCUGCUGAGGGAUCGGGAGGGAGUGGGGUCGGCAUAGGAGAUCGCUUCAAGAUUGAGGGGCGUGCAGUUGUUCCAGGGGUGAAGCCUCAGGACUGGAUCUCGGCGGCCCGAGUGCUGGUAGACGGAGAAGAGCACGUCGGUUUCCUUAAGACAGAUGGGAGUUUUGUGGUUCAUGAUAUACCUUCUGGAUCUUAUGUAGUGGAAGUUGUAUCUCCAGCUUACAGAUUUGAUCCCGUUCGAGUGGAUAUCACUUCGAAAGGAAAAAUGAGAGCAAGAUAUGUGAAUUACAUCAAAACAUCAGAGGUUGUCAGACUGCCCUAUCCUCUCCAAAUGAAAUCUUCAGGUCCACCUUCUUACUUUAUUAAAAGGGAAUCGUGGGGCUGGACAGACUUUCUAAUGAACCCAAUGGUUAUGAUGAUGGUUCUUCCUUUAUUGAUAUUUGUGCUUCUGCCUAAAGUGGUCAACACAAGUGAUCCUGACAUGAGACGGGAAAUGGAGCAGUCAAUGAAUAUGCUGAAUUCCAACCAUGAGUUGCCUGAUGUUUCUGAGUUCAUGACAAGACUCUUCUCUUCAAAAUCAUCUGGCAAAUCUAGCAGCGGCAGCAGUAAAACAGGCAAAAGUGGGGCUGGCAAAAGGAGGUAGUCAGGCCGUCCAGAGCUGGCAUUUGCACAAACACGGCAACACUGGGUGGCAUCCAAGUCUUGGAAAACCGUGUGAAGCAACUACUAUAAACUUGAGUCAUCCCGACGUUGAUCUCUUACAACUGUGUAUGUUAACUUUUUAGCACAUGUUUUGUACUUGGUACACGAGAAAACCCAGCUUUCAUCUUUUGUCUGUAUGAGGUCAAUAUUGAUGUCACUGAAUUAAUUACAGUGUCCUAUAGAAAAUGCCAUUAAUAAAUUAUAUGAACUACUAUACAUUAUGUAUAUUAAUUAAAACAUCUUAAUCCAGAAAUCAAA